GCCUCAGGGAAGCGAGCCCGGGCGCCGGCGGGCGGCCGUCGCGUCUGACAGACCACUGCAGACCACGGGCCGAGGCCCAGCGCCCGUCCGCAGCGCGGCCGGCAUGGCGGCGACAAGGAGCCCCACGCGGGCAAGGGAGCGGGAGCGGUCUGGCGCUCCCGCCGCAGAAGAACCAGCUCCUGAGGUCUCUGGCUAGGAUGCUACUAUAGGAAGGAGUAAAGGCGGUAGUAGGGGAGCCAGAACCCCACCUCCAGGAAGGCCUCUCCACCGGGAAACUUGAGAGAAGUGACCAAGUUCACUCCUGGAUGCUAGCUACAAGCCAAGCCUUAGACACUGUCUGGAGAAUGGCAAAAGGCUUUGUGAUGUUGGCAGUUUCAUUUCUGGUGGCUGCCAUCUGCUACUUCCGGAGGCUACAUUUAUAUUCAGGGCACAAGCUGAAAUGGUGGAUUGGAUAUCUGCAGAGAAAAUUCAAAAGGAACCUCAGUGUGGAGGCAGAGGUUGAUUUACUCAGUUAUUGUGCAAGAGAAUGGAAAGGAGAGACACCCCGUAACAAGCUGAUGAGGAAGGCUUAUGAGGAGCUAUUUUGGCGGCAUCACAUUAAAUGUGUUCGACAAGUAAGGAGAGAUAACUAUGAUGCUCUCAGAUCAGUGUUAUUUCAGAUAUUCAGCCAGGGCAUCUCUUUUCCAUCAUGGAUGAAAGAAAAGGACAUUGUUAAGCUUCCUGAAAAACUGCUGUUUUCACAAGGUUGUAAUUGGAUUCAGCAGUACAGUUUUGGUCCUGAGAAGUAUACAGGCUCGAAUGUGUUUGGAAAACUACGGAAAUAUGUGGAAUUAUUGAAAACACAGUGGACUGAAUUUAAUGGCAUUAGAGAUUAUCACAAGAGAGGAAGUAUGUGCAACACCCUUUUUUCAGAUGCCAUUCUGGAAUAUAAACUUUAUGAAGCUUUAAAGUUCAUCAUGCUGUAUCAAGUCACUGAAGUUUAUGAACAAAUGAAGACUAAAAAGGUCAUUCCCAGUCUUUUUAGACUCCUGUUUUCCAGGGAGACAUCCUCUGAUCCUUUGAGCUUCAUGAUGAAUCACCUGAAUUCUGUAGGCGACACAUGUGGACUAGAGCAGAUUGAUAUGUUUAUACUUGGAUACUCCCUUGAAGUAAAGAUAAAAGUGUUCAGACUGUUCAAGUUUAACUCCAGAGACUUUGAAGUCUGCUACCCAGAGGAGCCUCUCAGGGACUGGCCGGAGAUCUCCCUGCUGACCGAGAACGACCGCCACUACCACAUUCCAGUCUUUUAAGUCCGCUGGGGGCCGAACAGCAGUGCUCACCAGUGACGGUGGUCACAGUUGCAAUAAAGUCUCUCUCUGAAACCAAAGCUAGCAUUUCAGCAUGGAAGGAAUUAGGACCUUUUCUUCAGGAUUACAGGUACACUGGAUGCAGCCAUGCAUGGAUGGUUUUUCUUUAUUUUUCAGUGAUUUCCUCUGAAGCAGCUGCACUGAUACAUUUGGGAGUUGGUGGCUUGACUUUGUCCAUAAGGGGCGUGGCCACUUCACAUGAUGGCGGGCCUUUAAGAGCACAAAGAAGUUUAAUAUGGACAACAACAGGAAAAAGCAAGAAGAAAACAAGUAGGGAAAAACAGCUAACCUGGAGAGAAAGAAUUUCUUUAACCUUUAUGUUCUUCAUUAAAAAUCUUAUCUUGGACUGAUUUGAGGGAUUUUUAGAAACAUGGCCUUAUUUUAUAUAAGCAUUACCUUCCCAGGAAUCUUUGUUGUAUAUUAAUUUUUGAUAACCAUUUGAUUAACUUUAAAAUUAAGUAUAUGUGUGUAUAUAUACAUAUGUAUGUUUAUAUACACACAUGUAUCUGUAUAGUUUUAUAUAUACAUAUAUACACAUAGACAUACAGAGAACCACUACUUUGUAAUAGUGUACAGUUUGUUUUAUAUCUCUUUACUUUUUUUGUUACUAUUUUAUCUGGCCAGCUUAAUAGUUUUAUUUAGAUUUUUUAAAAUUCUGUAGAUUAAAGCAAAUGACAGUUAUUGAACUAUCACAAAACUAUUAAACUGUGGUACAUUUAAUGUGUAUUUAAUGUGUGGAAUCUCAUUAUGGUAGGCAGAAUAAUGCCCUAUGCUCCCCAAAGAUGUCUGUGUCUGAAUCCUCAGAGCCGUAAAGGGCUAAAUGGGUUAAAUGGGAAAGGAGAAUUAAGGUUGCAGGUGGAACUGAGAUGCUAAUCCAAUGAUGCUGAAAUAGGGAGAUUUUUCUAGAUUCUCCAGGUGGACGCAGUGUAAUCAGAAUGGUUCUUAAAAGUGGAAGAGGGAAUUGGAAGAGUGUCAGAGUCAGAGGGGAAUGUGAAAUAUGGAAGAACGGUUAGAGAGAGAUGCACCAUUGCUGGCUUUGAAGAUGGAGGAAGGGGCCAUAAGCCAGGGAGUUGCAGGCAGCCUGUAGAAUUGAGACUGGAAAGGAAACAGAAACUUCCCCAUAGCCUCCAGAAGGAACGCAGCCCUGCCAACACCUUGAUUUUAGCCCAGUGAAGCCUGUGUUGGACCUCUAAUCUGCAGAACUGUAAGAUAAUAGAUUUGUGUUUAAGCCACUAAGUUUGUGGUAAUGUGUUGUAGCAACAGAAAACUAGUAUUCUCAGGCUAGUUUUUGGUCGUCUUUAUUUUGGAAAUACUUUUCUAGUUUAAUUUGAUAGUUUUUUUUUUGGAGGUACUUUGCUAGUCUGUUUUGAGUUUCAGUACAUAAGAAUAAUUUUUAAAAUCUUGCUAAUUAUAUAUUACUUCAAAGUCACAAAUCCCUUUCUAAGAAUGACUUACUUCACGAGAUAUUUAGCACUAUCAUUUUCCCAGAUGUUCAUAUUAUUUCUGCAAUAAAUUAAAAGGGAGUGUGUCAAAUGCUGUCAUGUCUGAAAUUAGCAUUCAUAUUCUUUUGCAAUGGGGAUGAUCAGUCGUGUGUACUACAUGAACCAUGUCUGAUGGUAGCUUGUUCCCACUGUCAUUUUGUUUUCUGGUUGAAGAUUAAUGAGCUCAGCCACAGAAACAAGAGUUCUUCAUUGACCUCUACAGUCCCUGCCUGUUUGGAAACAUCUAUGGUUUUGUAUAACCCCUGUCAUUUAACUGACAGUGUUAGAAGAUAUCCCCCUGAUGUGUUACUGUAACCAAGAAAGCAUGAACGUUACCCUUUCUGGUGACAGCCUGCCAUGGGCUGCUGUGGCUGAUACUUAUAGAAUUGUUGCUCCAAAAUUUUGGCUCCACUUGAGCUGUCCAGAAGUGUACCUGACAUUUGUGUAUUACCACUCACCUUGGAUCUCCUUACUAGUGUAAUUAUUUCCACAUCAAUCCAGGACUGAAAGGAAAAAUUUUUUCACCAGGAUUGGCAGCCUGUAGCUCUGUGACCUCAGUCAACCCAUCAUGUUGUGUUGUGGGCGGGGGGCAAGAAUUCUUUAGAGAACCAAGUUGCGAGAAAGAUUUCAAUCCAGUGAAAGUAAAAAGUAAGAAGACAUUUAGAUAGUUGCUAUAUUUUGGGAAGAUGUCAAAACAGGUUUUUAGGGAGGAGGUAUGAGGUGUUGUGUUGUUUUGUUUGUUUUUAUUCAGUUGUAUAAUGAAUAUAACAAAUUAAGUAGCCAGAAGGAGCUGCAUGUAAAUUAGCACCACUUUUAAAUGUCAACAAUAAAUUUGAGGUGAGCUUCCUGGGUGAUGCCAACAUUUAAAUGUCUUUCUAACCGUAUAUGUUUUAAAUGGUGAGAGAACUAUAGCAAAAAUGGAAACAUAAUGCCCUCGUCGUUUUUUGAUUUUAGGAUAAGUUUCUCUCUCAAAUUUUGGCCUUACGUGUCCAUACUGAGGGGUUGUAUGCAUAUUAGUACAAGGCUGACUUUUACUGUGGUAAAAUACACAUAACAUAUAGUUUAUAUUUUAACAAUUUUUUUUUUUGAGACGGAGUUUCACUCUUUUUGCUCAGGCUGCAGUGCAGUGGCACAAUCUCGGCUCACUGCAACCUCUACCUCCCAGGUUCAAGCGAUUCUCCUGCCUCAGCCUCCCGAGUAGCCGGGAUUACAGGUGCCCACCACUACGCUCGACUAAUUUUUUGUGUUUUUAGUAGAAACGGGGUUUCACCAUUUAGCCAGGCUGAUCUGAACUCCUGACCUUGGGCGAUCCGCCUACCUCGGCAUCCCAAAGUGCUGGGAUUACGGGUGUGAGCCACUGCGCCCGGCCCUAACAAUUUUUAAGUGACAGUGACAUUAAGCAUAUUCACAUUGUUGUGCAACCCUCACCACCAUCCACCCUCAGAACUUUUUAAAAUCUCCAAGACUGACUUUUUUUCAAAGCAGGCAACUUUAAUUCCCUACCUGGUAUCUGGAUUCCUUUUCCUUUUCAUGCUAUCUUUUCAUCAUACCUCUUCUAAUCUGAGUAUUUCCUCUGGGCUUAAAAGAGCCUCAGUGGAGAAGUACAACCUAAGAGGGAGUUAGGUACAACCUAGGAGGGAGUCAGGAGGAGAGAGUUAGGUUAGUUAGUACAACCUAAGAGGGAGUUAAAUGGAUCAGGAAAAUCGUGUUUUAUCUCCAAAGUAAAAUGAUAACUAUGGGUGGCUUCUGGGCUCAAUUUAGAAUAUUAUCAUUGAAAAGUCCCCAAGAAACUAUUAAUUCAGAGCCACCCUGGUGAGUUGAAUUUCUUGAAUGUCUUCAUGGUCUUGAACCAAAGUCAUUUCCACCCAAGGGAGAGUCAGGUGAAAGUCCCCAGGGCCCUCUCUAGGGGACCGGAGACCUCCAGACUAAGCUGGUGGAGGAUGGGCUCAACCUCCAUGAGAGAAGAGCAGCCAGGAUCAGGGGGCAUUAACGUUAAUUUUCCCAGGACUUUUCUGCAAAUGGGUAUUGGAUGGAAAUAUUUGUUCUCAGUCAGAUGAGUUUCUCCUAUUUUAGUGAGACCAAAGAAAGACAAUUUUAAUUGUGUCCAAGCUGACUUUUUUGAAUGCUCUGGAAAUGUUGGAAUUCCACAUCAAAGUACGUAACUGUUUUAAACUGAUAACUAACCCAAUAUGUGAAAAUAUAUGCAAGCAUGAAUAAAGGGUUGACUAAUUCCAGAAUUAGCAAUAAUUUUCUCUUAAAUAGCAAAUUUCUAAAGCUGUAUGAUUCUCUUUGCAAGAAUGUUUUUCACACUGCUUAAUAAGACCAGUUAAUGUGUAAAACAGAAAAAAGUAUAUAUAUAUCAUAUGUCUUUUCAUGCAUCUGAAACUUUAACUGUCUAUAGGGUUGCUUGUCAUAGUUGAACAUUAUUUAAUUAACUUAUUGACUAUAUAUGGGUAUACUUUUCUCUAUAGCCAUUCACUUUUUUAAAGUUUUAAUUAUUUAAUUGACAAAUUAGCUAUUCAUUUUCCUUCAAAUCCUGUUUUUAUCACAAUGUCCAUUUUACAGCUAGACACAAAAUUUAGUGGGUCCAAAUUGUUCAAUCACUUCUAUGUUAUUUGUUCAGAAUAGUGGAUCUUUGCUUAAUUCACUUCUGUUUUAAUCCCAUCAUAUUCCUUUAGGCCAAGAAAAGGAAAGCUGAUUUGGAUUAUAUUUAUGCUUAAUAUCAACAUGGUUUAUAAGUGGACAGAAAAACACUCACUCACGUAUUCAGCCACGUAUGGUCUGGAGUGCUCUGUAGAACAGCCCGAAGUGUACACCAUGUCUCUGCACUUGAAGCUCAUGGAAUGUGUUGGAGGAGACUCAAGCUCCAUGUGGGAACAGUGUGGCCCAAGAGCCAGCAUGGAGGAGGGCUGUGUGAGCAGACUGCUAUAGAAUGCUAAAGUUAUAAUCCUAGCUGGUGUCUCGUUCUGUUUAAAAAAAUCAAAUUUCUGUAUGUAAUUGACGUAUUGGUCCUUAUAGUCAGUACCAUCAGGUCUUAGAUUGUUAAGUCAUUUUGCUGCCACCAGACCAGUGAGAGUCACUCACUUAUUUGUAAUGAUUCUUGGGAAGUUUAGUCAAGAGAAUAUCCUUGAAUAAAGAAGUACAUGUUUUAAGUAUUUUCAUCGUAGUCUAGAUGGGCUGUAAAACCCAUUUCCACACGAGUAUAAAUUUAAAACAGAAACAUCAAGGUGUCAGCAAUCAUGAUUUUGUUUUGCUUGUUCACAAGUUUGAAAAGGUGCAUGAGGCACCAAUCAGUGACACUGGAAUGCUUUAAGGAUGGUUUGUGACUUUACCCCAUUGUGCCUUAUCAUUUGUCAGCAAACUUACUGGGCCAAACACAAAUGGCUGAGACACUCCUGGCCCAUUUCUUGUCAUCGCUGCCAUCCCCAAAGACAGACUCUGGGAAACAACUUGGGAACUGCUUCAAGUCCAUGCCAGGUCAUGGCUUCGUCCGCCUCCCAGCAUGUACCUGGACUUCCUUUGGGUGCCGGCUUUUCUGCUGGACUAAGAUUCAUGGAAAGAACCCCAGGGCAAGGUGAGGAGAAGCAGCUGGUACAGACUGAUGACGAAGGAGAGGACCAGAAAAGCUGCUUGGGUGUGGUGGAAGUUUCAGUGUAAUGUGAUUCCUAGUAGGCACAUCUGUGACUCCCUUAAAUAAAAAGGGCCAGAGAUGAGGGGACGCCUGGUGAAAAUGGUGUUUGUUGUAACAUCUUGGUAUCAUUGUGGGUAAGUAGAACAAAUAUUUACAUCUGUUAUGAAAAGCUACCUUUAGCCGUAGAUAAACAUUAAAAGGAAGACUCAGCCCCAGAGUAUAUUUGAUCUAUUGGUUAACUCAUCUGUCAGCAAAUGGUUAAGUAAGUAAAAUUAAUUUUUCCAUUUGGUGUGUAUUUCACAGGGUAACAAUGAAGUGCUCCAAUCUGCUUGUGAGACCAGUUAGAUUAGUAGUUGCAGUUGAGACCAUUCCUCCUGUAUGUCUUUACAAGCAAAUUGAAACGACAUGCUCUUCUUUGUACUAUACAGAAGGACACACCACAGAUCCUCUUUUUAAAGCAGGUAAUAAAGUAGCUUUUUCCUUUUGAAACAUCAUUGUAAAACAGUGCUUUUUAAACUAUCCAUGGUAAAGGAUGAGUUUUAAAAAUUCUAAUCCUUUGCAGGUUGGUAGUUUUAUAAAUACGAUAAAAAUAUAGCACCAAGAUUAGAUUGUUAUAAAAGUUUCUAAACACUUUCAGUUUCUGUACUUAAUCUUGCAGUGUGGUAAUAAAGACUUCUACACUUUAGUAGCACUAAAA